GACGCCACGGACAUGGUGGCCGAGACCGGCGGGGUGGGGGACGUGUCGCGCGGCCGGGUGGCCUCGGUCGGUACCCUGGGCGCGGAGCAGCUGCCUCAUUAGUAUUCGUACCCACGAGGCGGCGCAGCGGGCCCUCGGGGACAGCGAGCGUCGCGGCCAUGGCUUAUCACUCGGGCUACGGAGCCCACGGCUCCAAGCACAGGGCCCGGGCAGCCCCGGAUCCCCCUCCCCUCUUCGAUGACACAAGCGGUGGUUAUUCCAGCCAGCCCGGGGGAUACCCAGCCACAGGAGCAGACGUGGCCUUCAGUGUCAACCACUUGCUUGGGGACCCAAUGGCCAAUGUGGCUAUGGCCUAUGGCAGCUCCAUCGCAUCCCAUGGGAAGGACAUGGUGCACAAGGAGCUGCACCGUUUUGUGUCUGUGAGCAAACUCAAGUAUUUUUUUGCUGUGGACACAGCCUACGUGGCCAAGAAGCUAGGGCUGCUGGUCUUCCCCUACACACACCAGAACUGGGAAGUGCAGUACAGUCGUGAUGCUCCUCUGCCCCCCCGGCAAGACCUCAACGCCCCUGACCUCUAUAUCCCCACGAUGGCCUUCAUUACUUACGUGCUCCUGGCUGGGAUGGCACUGGGCAUUCAGAAAAGGUUCUCCCCGGAGGUGCUGGGCCUGUGUGCAAGCACAGCGCUGGUGUGGGUGGUGAUGGAGGUGCUGGCCCUGCUCCUGGGCCUCUACCUGGCCACCGUGCGCAGUGACCUGAGCACCUUUCACCUGCUGGCCUACAGUGGCUACAAAUACGUGGGAAUGAUCCUCAGUGUGCUCACGGGGCUGCUGUUCGGCAGCGAUGGCUACUACGUGGCGCUGGCCUGGACCUCAUCGGCGCUCAUGUACUUCAUUGUGCGCUCUUUGCGGACAGCAGCCCUGGGCCCCGACAGCAUGGGGGGCCCCGUCCCCCGGCAGCGUCUCCAGCUCUACCUGACUCUGGGAGCUGCAGCCUUCCAGCCCCUCAUCAUAUACUGGCUGACUUUCCACCUGGUCCGGUGACCCCCUGGCCCCAGAUGGCACUGAGUUUUUCAUUCAUUGAAGAUUUGAUUUCCUUGA